CUCCCCGCCUAGGUGCUGGCCGAGCGCGGGGCGGGCAGGCGAGCGCGGCGGCGGCGGCGAGCGUGGUGAGUGUCUGCCCGGCGGCUCCCUUCUGCUGCGCCCAUCCGAACGCGGCCGGGCUGCGGGGGCGAGAGGUGCUGCGGCGGCCGAGGGAGGUGACAGCUGCCCGAACAACGUGGCCUGGCGGGCGGGAGGGGGGGUCCUGGACCAGCGGAUGCUCCGAUCCGCGGCUGCUCUGGCGUGAGACGCCGUGCUCGGCCCCGACGGUUCCGGGCGCGCUCCCCGCACAUACGUGUCCCCGAGGGUGGGUGUCCGGGGCCCGAGCCCAAGGAAGAAAGGCCGACCCGUGUGGGACGCACACGUGGGAGUUCACCGGACAUCUGUGGACACGUGCGUGGCCGGAGUCGCGGUGGCCAGGCGGAGGACGGAGCGGUCGGCUGAGCCCCAGCAGUAGGGCAGGGGCCUGAGCCGGCCUCCGAGCGCAGAGAGCGGCCCCCAACCCGCUUCUCCUUUGUCCUCUGGCCGAGGCAUCGCGCAGUUGGAGUCCCCUUCCGGGACCCUCCAGCCAGCAGGAUAGAAAGCACCGCCCCAAGAGGACGGGGACAGCGGGAGAUUGAAUGGGGAGCCGCCGGCCAGACUCGGAGCCUCACCCCCAUUGCCUUUCUUGGGGGUAGGAGGAGCCUGGCGGCUUCUUGGGUGGAGGAUUUUACCCCUGCAGAUUCGGAAGCAGCGGUAUCUUCCUGUGGGGUGGUCUCUGCUCUCCUGCUGUCUCCCUGGCUUGCCUGUGGCCUCAGUUCACCUGACUAUGAAGGGGGGACAGUGACGGCUCACAGCCCGGGGCCCGGCUGGGGCUGCAGGGUUUCUAUAGCAACAUCAGUGCAGGGGGAGGGCCCUGGCCAGCUGUCUCAUAAACCAGGGGUGGGAACUGCCGAGUGAGGGCAGAGAAAGGCGGGGUUGGCGUUCAGAGGGAACCCCUGCCGGUUCUUCCCCAGGCAGAGCCCCUCACUGUCAUCAUUCUCCACCCAGAAGCUCCUCUCCGCUGCACUGGGUGACGUGCGGGCCCAGGCCUGCCUCUCCGCCCUGGGAUCUCUGGGCCUGCUUCUCUUCUUGGGACGAAUGGCCGCUCCCCACCUCGGUCGGCCUGACUUCCAGGAUUGCCCCUAUCAUGCAGGUGUCCUCAUCCCAGACUGGAGAUAGGCUCCCAGGAGGAAGGGGGUUGCUCAGUCCCUGGAGGGCCAGGGUACACCCCUGGGAGGGACUAGAGUGGAGAUGAAGGGCCCAGCGCAGCCCGGAGAGCUGUGGCCAGUCUGCACCCGAAGAGUGGGGCGGCAGGGGUGGGGGGGGCUAGGAGGGAUCAGGUAGAAGUUCAGAGGUCAGCUUGUCACCACCACUGGCUGAGGCAGGGAAAGGCAGGUCUGACGGUGAAGCCCUGAGUGGGACGGGUGGUGGGGCAGAGGGCUCUGGGCAUGCCAGCUCGUGUGCCCUCUGGACCUGCCAGGUGAGCAGGGCCUGUGGGUGGCAACAGUGGCCUCUGGCACCCAGCUAGCUCUUCCCUGUGGACAGCAGGCCUUUUUUGUGGCCCAGCAUGAGGCUUCCCUGACAUGCAUCUGCCCCUAGCAGACACACAUCCCACAGACACGAGUGGGUGUUAGCCCAUCUCUGCUCCACAGCACCGGAUUCCCUGUCCAGGCUGCCGGAAGCCUCUGCUUGCCCAAAGUGAAAGAGAAAGUGCCCCCCCACCCAAGCCCGCCCCACCCCGCCCCACGGCCAAUCCCUGCGGCCCCUCGCCUCCUCCCCCGGCAGCUUCCCCUUCUGUGUGAGUGCUGGGCUGGAGUGUGGAAGAGCCAUCCAGAGUGAGUGCCUGGGGCAGAGUGAGAGCAGGACCAGCGGGCAGGUGGCGGAGCGGGGGUCGGUGGUGGAUGGCCCAGCCCUGGAAAGCCGAGGUGAAGGUUACGAGUCCCUGAGGAUCUGUGGGUGUGAGCCAGCCGCGUGGCCCUGGGCAACGGCGCUGCCGGACAGAAGUGGCGGUUGCUGACGCCUGGAAAUUCCCCUGAAGGUGGAGCACCACCCAACCCCCCUGGGUCCCACCCUCCCUCAAGGCCUCCUCCACCUCCACCUCCACCCCGCCUGGCCUGGCGUCCACCUCUGCGGCUCCUACCUGGGUGCAAUCGAGUUAAAUGGCUGAUAAGCAGAUCAGCCUGCCAGCCAAGCUCAUCAAUGGCGGCAUCGCCGGGCUGAUCGGUGUCACCUGCGUGUUUCCCAUCGACCUGGCCAAGACCAGGCUGCAGAACCAGCAGAACGGCCAGCGCGUGUACACGAGCAUGUCCGACUGCCUCAUCAAGACCGUCCGCUCCGAGGGCUACUUCGGCAUGUACCGGGGAGCUGCUGUGAACUUGACCCUCGUCACCCCCGAGAAGGCCAUCAAGCUGGCAGCCAACGACUUCUUCCGACAUCAGCUCUCUAAGGACGGGCAGAAGCUGACCCUGCUUAAAGAGAUGCUGGCGGGCUGUGGGGCUGGCACCUGCCAGGUGAUCGUGACCACGCCCAUGGAGAUGCUGAAGAUCCAGCUGCAGGAUGCAGGGCGCAUUGCCGCCCAGAGGAAGAUCCUGGCUGCCCAGGGCCAGCUCUCGGCCCAGGGGGGUGCCCAGCCCUCAGUGGAGGCUCCAGCUGCCCCUCGGCCCACGGCCACCCAGCUGACCCGCGACCUGCUGCGGAGCCGUGGCAUUGCCGGUCUCUACAAGGGACUCGGGGCCACGCUGCUCAGGGAUGUCCCCUUCUCUGUGGUGUACUUCCCGCUCUUUGCCAACCUGAACCAGCUGGGCCGCCCGGCGUCCGAGGAGAAGUCGCCUUUCUACGUGUCCUUCCUGGCCGGCUGUGUGGCUGGGAGUGCCGCCGCUGUGGCCGUCAACCCCUGUGAUGUGGUGAAGACGCGGCUCCAGUCACUUCAGCGAGGCGUCAACGAGGACACCUACUCUGGGAUCCUGGACUGUGCCAGGAAGAUCCUGCGGCACGAGGGCCCCUCGGCCUUCCUGAAGGGCGCCUACUGCCGCGCGCUGGUCAUCGCGCCCCUUUUCGGCAUCGCACAGGUGGUCUACUUCCUGGGCAUCGCGGAGUCCCUGCUGGGGCUGCUGCAGGACCCCCAGGCCUGAGCCCAGCACCCGCUCCACCCCAGCCAGCUGGGCAGGGCCGGUGUGGGGCUGGAGCCAGGCAGCUAGCCCAGGACGGAGCAAGGGAAGACCCCUCCCCAGCCCUCCCGUCGGCAGGGGCAGCAGGGGGCAGGGUGCAGGGUCCACAUAGGUGGUGCACACGCAAGCCCCCCGGGGUGCUGCCUGCACCGUUGGGAUCAAUGUCUCAUUUAUGUAGAAAAUGCAGAAAUCUUUACAUUCCUCAAGCUAGCCCCUGCCCCAAUCCUGCCCUGGCCUGAACACCCCCAGGGACAGAGCUGGUCUCUGGGCUGGGGGCCCCCGGGCCUGGGCCGGGCAGGCUGGACCAUACCCCCAGUCCACCAGCUCCAGUCUCCACAGCCAUCCUGGCCCACACAGGCACCCCACACAAACCUAUUUAUUGAAUCUGCUGGACCCAAGCGGCUCUCCAGCCCUUCCGUCCUUCCCCAGCCGCUCUUGUCGCCUUGGCAGGACUUGACUCUGCCUCCCUGGCCAGCCUUGCAAGAGGACUGGGGUCUCCUGCCCUCUCUGUUGAGCCAGGAAUCCCAAGUGAGGGGUUGCCCUGAGGUCUGACUCUUGGGGCAAGCCCGCCACCCACUGUGGGACUUUCUGGUGGGCUCCUCAGCUCCCACCCCAGGCUGGGGCCCAGAUUGUGAGGUCUGUGUGCAUGUGUGUGUGUAUGUGUGUGUGCAUGCGUGUGUGUGUUGUGGGGAUCUGGCCUGGCCCUUGGGGAUGGGGCUGCUGGGGACUGCCCCCCUUCCCGCCGUGGCCAGGCGCUCUGUGUGCUGUGUGUGCCCCAGGCUCUGUUGACCCCGUCCAGGAACUAACUUACCCAGCUUGGUCUCUCCUGAGUCCUCCACCCUGGCCUGGGAUUGGCCAGGGAGCAGGGCGGGCAUUGGGACCAGUGUGGAGCCUGAGGGUGCCUGCCCUGCUCUGGAGGGAGGGCCAGGAGCUGCCACACCCCCAAGUCCUCUCAGGGCCCACCCUCCUUUUUCAGCCUCUGCAUAAGGCCCCUGGGUACACUGCAGAAGCCCCAUCCUUCCCGCCUCCGGGCAUAAGGCCCCUGACCACACUUCAGAAGCCCCAUCCCCCCUGCCACCGGGCGAUCCCUGCUGUGAGCCGAAGCUCUCCCUGCCCCGCCCUGGCCAUGUGAUCGUGUUGGUGACAGACCCUGAUGUGCUGGUGCUGUGUCCCCAAAACCGGGGCCCUCCACAGAGGCCCCUUCCCAGCGACACUACCUGGGGCUCAGGCCUGGACCCCCCCAGUUCACGGUUGCUCCUGGGAGCUGCCCCUCCCGUCACAUCAGAACCUUGGAAGCUGCUGCUGCUGCUUACAGAAUUAUAUUUUUUUCUUUUGAAGAGUUUUAAGAAGUUGUAACUUUUUGUGUCUUGUCAUGUCAGAGAAUAAAUAAAUAUUCUAAGUAGA